AUGCUUCCCCGGCGCCCUGAGCCCCUGACCGCGGCUGAGCCUGCGGUGGCCUGCGCCGGAGGAUCCCGGACAACGCGCAUUUCCUGCGCCCCCGGAAGCGGCGGUAACGCCUGGCCCUGCCCCCGGCAGAGGCGGAAGCACAGUCGCUCUGAGGUCGCCCGUGGCCGCAGGUGCCUCAGCCCAGCCGCGCGCCUUGGCCCUUGGCCGCCUACUCCUACCGCCCCGGCCUUGGGCGGCCCUGGGCCUGCUGCGGGCGCGGCGCUGCCCGACCAGAGCUUCCUGUGGAACGUCUUCCAGAGCUGCCACCUGGCACCGCCCCGGCACCUCCCGCCUCCCCCGCAGCUGCCCCGGACCCGUGUCCCGACCCCCGCGGCCAACCCCGUUCCCUGCCGGUUGCCCCGCGGCCUCCCCCGUCACCUGCCGGGUCCCCAGCGGCCUCCCCCGUCCCCUGCCCCGACCUCCGCCGUCUCCCCCGCCCCUGCCCGGACCCCCGCGGGCGCCCCCGAACCCUACCCCGACCGACGCGGCCGCCCCCAUCCCCUGCCCCGACCCCCGCGGCCGCCCCCAUCCCCUUCCGGGUCCCCCGCGGUCUCCCCCGUCCGCUGCCCGGUCUCCUGGGGCCGCCCCUGCCUCCUGCCCGGUCCCUGUCCUGUGCGUCGGGCGCUUCCCAAGGUGCAGAGGGCGCCACUGCAGACCCGAGGUCGCGGCCACCGGCUCCUGGGCCAGGCCCCGUUUCUCGCCUCGAGCCGUCGGGGGAGGGUCUCCAGGGUGCUUGUUUGGGGAAAGCGGAAACAGACUGUCUGGGCCGCUGUUAAAAUGUCAGCAGCCAAGGAAGAAGCAGCGACCUGGCGUCUGCUCGGGCCAGGUGACCUUUAUGGCGGCGCCUUCUGUCCCUGGUCGCUUUUCCACUGAAUGAAUGACCGAAACUGUAGUAACUCAUGGCCAGGGAAUGGCUUAGUUAUCUGAGGGAAUCUUGUCUUGUCUGUGAAAAAGGGAAACUGGUGCAAAUGGGAAUUCAGACAGGUCAGGAGGGGAAGGAAGGGAAGGAUUGAGGUGGGAAAAGAGAGAGAAAGAUGAUUGUCCUCUUAGGGGAAGAACACACUUGGACGUGGCUCCUGGGGCACUUCCUUGAUUCCGCUGUACUCCUCAGCGGGACCGGAGAGGCGGAGGUUCCAGGAGGGAGCCUUCCAGAGUCGGUGCAGGGUUGACAGGAGACGUUUGUUUUGCUUUUCCUGAACUUUCGAUCGCCAGCUUGUUUGGUCUUCUUGAUGUUAUAGGGUUGAUAGAGAGGAGUGGAGUGAUAUCGGACACCCAGCUUCAGCAAGCUCUCUCCAAGGGUGAGUGGGCCAGUGGGACCUGGGUCUCCGGACCAAGAAGCCGCGAGCCUGCCCUGCUCACAGUGGAUAACUUUCUUUCUGAAGUUGAUUUUCCAAGGACAAAGGAAUCAUUAGGACAAAUUAUUACUGCUUCAUGGUGGAGAUGCUUCUGGUUUAUUUUGUGGCUACCGCUGUUACUGCUUGGAGUGCCUCACCGAGCCAGCUAACAACGGCGUGCGUGAGCGCAGGGAAAGGCUUCUUGAGAAAUGAAAACUAGGUUGUAGGUUUAGGAGGGGAAUAGGAAGGUUAGCUCUGUCCAGCCGAAAGCCUUUUGGUAAGUUGGGGGUCCUUGAAUUUCCUGGGUGACUGCAUCUUGGUGACUUCUCUGAAUAGACCUUCGAGGGCACUGGGGGGUGAUUGUUGGAGGGCUUGGGGAGCUCAGGCAGCACUUGUGUGGGAACGUGGCUGUUACAGGAACUGCAGAAACUGGGACUGGGUUCCUGGGGAAAGGAUUGGGGGUGUUGGAGGCGCUGGCAGGGGAGUUAUGGGGAGGCGUUCUUAUCAGUGUGCGAAUAUUGGGCGUUCAGGCAGCGGGAAAUCUGGGUCCUUGGCGUGUUGUGAGCUCCCUGGAGUUACGUUCUUGCCAGUUUCAGCUCAAUUGAUCCCCCUCCCCUGAGCUAUCAUUGGAUACAUUUUACUUCAUUGAACACCUGACUGCUGCUUUUUCUGUAAUCCCUCAGGGGCAGUCAUCUUUUCUGAUUCUGUGUAUAGUUUGCCUUUCCAGAUCCGUGCCAUUUAAGCUAGAAAAGGGGUCAGUUUUGAGAUGUUGUGAAAAUGUUGAAAGGCUCCUCGUUAUUAGUGGGAAGUAUCUGAUGUUGCCAGAGACUGAACUGGGGCGCGGGGAGCACUACGGCUGCUAGACACUGCCUCACUGCGCUGUGGGUGGUGGGGGGGGAGGUGCUGGAUUCAGUCUUACUGCCUAAUGAUUUGUGAGGAUUUGUGUUUUCAGAGUAACAUGUUUACCUUAUGUUAUCAGUUCCUAAUAUGUGACGUAUGGGCCACAGAUGCUGGUGUAUUAUUUCACAUGCAUUUAUAUAGAUUGUUUUCAGGGAAUUCAGAAAUUCUGUUAUCUCUACACUAGUGAUUGUGCUUUCUUGAUUUUUCUCUUUUCAUUAUUCUUAAAUCCUCCUUUUUUUAUUUGCAUCUCAGUUUAUUUAUACUCGGGAAGUGCAAGACAUGGCGACUAGAAAGAGAUGUCAAGAGAACCCGGAAUCCAGUAGGCUACAAUUUGGCAAAUCUUAGCUUAAAACUUCCUAAAUGUUGACCACAGUGGAUGCAAAUGGCUCUGUGCAUCGUCUGUUCAAUAUGGUCAGGUGACCACCCAGGUUCACGUGGUUUGUCACCAGGGUGAUACGAGCCACACGGAGUGCCCUCCUCAGAGGCCAUGUCUCAGAGACGUUUAUUUUGAGUGGUUUUCCAGCGAGUGAUGCAAGAUUUAUGAUCCAUUUUAACAGCUGCUUUUUAUGCAUUUGCUCAAAUUUUUAGAUUUUAAGUUUAGUUUUAGGUUUUCUGUUAAUUUGCUCAACUAGGAGUGGUGGUCAAAUACUGGACCUCAUUAGCAUGGUAGCCUGCCCUCCUUGGCAGGCUCCACUGGAGUGCCUUGGGGCCUGCCUGGAUUCCAGUCCUGGCUCUACCAGUUUUGUGUCCUCGCCGUUACUGGGAGGGAGUAUUGAGGAAAUGCAUGCGAGGUGCCUCCGUGAUUCCUGGCACGGAGCAAGUGCUCAGUAAUUGUCAGCUGUGAGUAUUAGUAGUAGCUAAUACACUACUACUAUUCUUGGCUAACAAGCCAGCUCAAAGCUUUGAUGGUUUUCCAUUACCUGAUGAUGGUGAUGAUGGUUUCCACUUCCUGAACACUCACACCCCUGGGCUAGGCACUUAACCCAAAUCCAAGGUCAGCGUUAUUGUUUGGAGGUGGGGGAGACACCUCCUGCUCUGACUCGUGUGUUUGGGUUCCCGUAUUUUCACCAGAGGGUGUUAGUCCUGCCCCAGUUCAGCUGGUCCUCAAAGCGUAUAUAGCUCUUUAACCCUCAGCAAGUGUCAGUCAGAACAUAAUCUUGAUUUCAGCUGCUACUAAAUAUCUACCAGGAGCCUGCUUGAGAGAGAGAAUUGCCUGACAGGUGCUGAGUCCACCAUUCCUGAGAUACUUUGAAAUCAGUGUCUGGCUUAACCCAAGCUGUGUAUGGGGACCCUCUCACCGUGGUCCCAAUGGAGUCGCUUUUGUUAGGCGCCCCCCUUUACCUUGGGCUCUGAGCUUCCUCUGCCUUUCAUCUCUGCAGGAUGAAGCCCCACUCGCCCUUCAGGAUGCAAAGCCCUCCUCUAUAAAGUGCAUGCGGGGCCAGAUGCAGUGGCUCACGUCUGACCUCCCAACACUUUGGGAGGCCGAGGCAGGGGGAUCGUUUGAGACCAGCCUGGACAACAUUGUGAGACCCUGUUCCUUGAAUUGCCCUGGGAGAUUUCCUCAGCUUGUACUGGAGGAUGAAGCCCCACCCGCCCUUCAGGAUGCCAGCCUUGGCAACAUUGUGAGACCCUGUUUCUACAAAAAGUAAACGUGUAGUGGUGCACGCCUGUAGUUCCAGCUACUUGGGAGGCUGAGAUGGGAAGAUCACUUGAGCCUGGGAGGUUGAGGCUGCAUUGAGCUGAGAUCAAGCCACGGCACUCCAGCCUGGGAGACAGAGCGAAACCCCAUCUCAAAAAAACAAAGAAAGUGGAUGCGCGCUGCUCCUGCCAUUGGAUCAUCGCAGCAUUUUUCUUUUCUCUGAUAUGCGCCUUUUUCCUCAUCGUGGGGGCUCAUGUUUUCGUACUUUUCUCUCGCUACUAGAUUGUGAGCUGCGUGAAGGAAGGUUCAUAGUCGUGUUGUAUGUACAGGCACACAAAAUUUGUGCUUGGAUAGACACAUAUCAAUCCGCUUCCUUCUCCUCUCUGAGUUUCUUUAUUUAAAAAAAAAAUUAGAGAUGGAGUCUCACUGUCUUGCCCAGGCUGGUCUCAAACUCCUAGGCUCAAGCGAUCCUCCCGCCUCUACUAAUAUGAAUUAUUAGCCUAUACUAAUAUGAAUUCCUAUACUAAUAUGAUUGAAAUUAGUUUGACUUGUAUAAUAAUUGUUCUCCCAGAUUGGGCUUCUGUUUUGAUAGUAGAACUAAAUUAUUAGGCUAUUUCAAGAAAUUAAUAUAUUACUGGUAGAAAAACUGAAGCUACAAAAUGGCCUGGUUUCUCACUUCAGUUAAAUUUGUGCUUCUGAGUGCUUGUAUUGUAGGUGAAACCGCACUGAGAAGGUAUUUGUGGCCCGUAUGCUGAUUGAUUGAUGAGACUUCUUUGCACAGGAGAGCUGCUAAAAAUUAUUACGGUGAACAGGUAUGAAGAAGACUGUUCUCUGCCCUUCUUUUUGCAAUAAAAUGUUACAAACUAUCUUGAGAUUGAUCCCUUUUCGGGUGUUUGGGUUUUUUUUAACAUUCACAUAUUUCUUGGAAUUAUAAGAAAUUAACUUUGUGCUUCUGAAGUGGGUUUCCCUUAAUAUAACACUGAUGUAUUUGUAAGGGGCAUUUUUAAAGUUGUACUUUAAAAAAUAAUAAUUCUUACAUUCGUUUGAA